AGAAGAGACUACACAGCAGGCCCGAGACCAUCCUGAGAGGCCUGUGUGCAAGGCUGGCCCCCCGCUGGUGUCAGGACGGUGCCCACCACCCUCAAUGAAGAGGGGCUCCCUGUGCUUAGCUGCUUGUGUGGGGAACAAGGGCACUGUUUGAAGAAGCAAACAUGGUAGCAUCAAGCAUUCCUUGAAAUAUGGCUCCAAGGGAACAAUGAGACGUGCUCUUGGUCUUGGAAGCUCAUCAGAAUGUUUAGAGCUGGGGAGGCCUCCAAACGCCCAUUGCCUGGGCCGUCGCCCCCAAGGGUGCGGAGUGUGGAGGUUGCCCGGGGGAGGGCCGGCUACGGAUUCACGCUUUCGGGACAGGCACCCUGUGUGCUCAGCUGCGUCAUGAGAGGGAGCCCUGCGGAUUUCGUGGGCCUCCGAGCUGGAGACCAGAUACUUGCUGUCAAUGAAAUCAACGUGAAAAAAGCAUCUCAUGAAGAUGUAGUGAAAUUAAUUGGGAAGUGCUCUGGUGUCCUUCACAUGGUGAUUGCUGAAGGCGUCGGCCGCUUCGAAUCCUGUUCCAGUGAUGAAGAAGGGGGACUCUAUGAAGGAAAAGGCUGGCUGAAGCCCAAGCUGGAUUCUAAAGCACUAGGUAUAAACAGAGCAGAGCGAGUCGUGGAGGAAAUGCAGUCUGGUGGAAUUUUCAAUAUGAUUUUUGAAAACCCGAGCCUUUGUGCGAGCAAUUCAGAGCCCUUGAAAUUGAAACAAAGAUCCCUUUCAGAGUCGGCCGCAACUCGAUUUGAUGUUGGACAUGAAAGUAUAAAUAAUCCAAAUCCCAACAUGCUUUCUAAGGAGGAAAUAUCAAAAGUUAUUCAUGAUGAUUCGGUUUUCAGCAUUGGACUAGAAAGUCAUGACGAUUUUGCAUUGGAUGCAAGUAUUUUAAACGUGGCGAUGAUCGUGGGCUACUUAGGCUCCAUUGAGCUUCCUUCCACGAGCUCCAACCUGGAGUCCGACAGCUUGCAAGCCAUCCGCGGCUGCAUGCGGCGCCUGCGGGCAGAGCAGAAAAUCCACUCGCUGGUGACCAUGAAGAUCAUGCACGACUGUGUGCAGCUGAGCACUGACAAGGCUGGAGUCGUGGCCGAGUACCCGGCCGAGAAGCUGGCCUUCAGCGCCGUGUGCCCGGACGACCGGCGAUUUUUCGGGUUGGUUACCAUGCAGACGAAUGACGACGGGAGCCUGGCCCAGGAGGAGGAGGGCGCCCUGCGGACUUCCUGCCACGUGUUCAUGGUGGACCCAGACUUGUUUAAUCACAAGAUCCACCAAGGCAUUGCUCGGCGGUUUGGGUUUGAGUGCACGGCCGACCCAGACACCAAUGGCUGUCUGGAAUUCCCGGCGUCCUCCCUCCCCGUCCUGCAGUUCAUCUCUGUCCUGUACCGAGACAUGGGUGAGCUGAUUGAGGGCAUGCGGGCCCGCGCCUUUCUGGACGGGGACGCCGAUGCCCACCAGAACAACAGCACCAGCAGCAACAGUGACAGCGGCAUUGGGAACUUCCACCAGGAGGAGAAGAGCAACCGGGUCCUUGUGGUGGACCUGGGUGGGAGCUCGAGCAGACACGGCCCCGGAGGCAGCGCGUGGGACGGUGUGGGUGGGAGGGGUGCCCAGCCCUGGGGUGCUCCCUGGACUGGGCCCUUCUGUCCGGACCCCGAAGGGAGCCCCCCAUUUGAGGCCGCUCAUCAGACUGACAGGUUCUGGGACCUAAACAAGCACCUAGGGCCAGCCUCUCCUGUGGAGGUGCCCCCAGCUUCCUUGAGGAGCUCAGUCCCCCCUUCCAAGAGGGGCACCGUGGGUGCUGGCUGUGGUUUCAACCAGCGCUGGCUCCCGGUCCACGUGCUCCGGGAGUGGCAGUGCGGACACACCAGCGACCAGGACUCUUACACAGAUUCCACCGAUGGCUGGUCCAGCAUCAACUGCGGCACACUGCCCCCUCCUAUGAGCAAGAUCCCCGCAGACCGCUACAGGGUGGAGGGCAGCUUCGCGCAGCCCCCGCUGAAUGCCCCGAAGAGGGAGUGGUCCAGGAAGGCCUUUGGAAUGCAAAGCAUUUUUGGUCCCCAUCGAAAUGUUCGAAAGACUAAGGAAGAUAAAAAGGGCUCAAAAUUUGGGCGGGGAACUGGACUCACUCAGCCUUCUCAACGCACGUCUGCUCGGAGAUCAUUUGGGAGAUCCAAGAGAUUCAGUAUCACUCGCUCCCUUGAUGAUCUUGAGCCCUCAUCUCCAGCCUCAUCUCCAGCCCUCAUCUCCAGCCCUCAUCUCCAGCCCUCAUCUCCAGCCUCAUCUCCAGCCCUCAUCUCCAGCCUCAUCUCCAGCCCUCAUCUUCAGCCCUCAUCUCCAGCCUCAUCUCCAGCCUCAUCUCCAGCCUCAUCUCCAGCCCUCAUCUCCAGCCUCAUCUCCAGCCUCAUCUCCAUCCCUCAUCUCCAGCCCUCAUCUCCAGCCUCAUCUCCAGCCCUCAUCUCCAGCCUCAUCUCCAGCCCUCAUCUCCAGCCCUCAUCUCCAGCCUCAUCUCCAGCCCUCAUCUCCAGCCUCAUCUCCAGCCCUCAUCUCCAGCCUCAUCUCCAGCCCUCAUCUCCAGCCUCAUCUCCAGCCCUCAUCUCCAGCCCUCAUCUCCAGCCCUCAUCUCCAGCCCUCAUCUCCAGCCUCAUCUCCAGCCCUCAUCUCCAGCCUCAUCUCCAGCCCUCAUCUCCAGCCCUCAUCUCCAGCCUCAUCUCCAGCCUCAUCUCCAGCACGGGAUGAGCUCCUGGUGGCCAGCUGUGUUACGCCAGUCCCUGUCCAGAACCUCUCAGCACAGCUGACUUUUACACUCAUCUUUCCUUGCGGGGGGUUGGCACUGACACAUUGGAAACCUGAGUCACGAAUGUCGGCCUGGAUGCCUGGCAGCCUGCCACCUGUCUGCGUGCUGGAGGGCCCUUGGCUUCUGAGACUGGGCGAGCUGAGGAGGGCAAAGGCCUGUGUGGUGUUUGUCCCAACAGAGGGUUAUGGUGUGACAAGGAGGAGCAUCCCAAAGUCAGAUGGCCCCUACUGCUGUCCCAGGAGGACACUACUUUGGGCUCAAAAGUUGUCAGAAUAUAUUAUCUUAGGCUCCGCCAAGGAUAUGAAAUGAAUAUUAGCUGCUGCUGCUUUGAAAGGCUGUCAUUUUGGUUUUUGCCCUGGUUCAGUUCCUUCUGAUUUUAUUCAAGGUUGAAAAGCUCCUUGGAACACACACACACACACACACACACACACACACACACACACACACACUUUAAAGGGAGAAGCGCAGGUCUGUGUCUCAGCCCCAGGUGUGCUGCCCUCCCCGCAGACCGUGGUGGCUGCUCUGCCAGGCGAGGUUGCACGUGGGAGCUGGGCUGCAGUGAGGAGGGCACCAUGCUGAGGAGUGGAGAGGGAGAUGGAACAGGAGGGGACUGGGUCCCUCUGUGCAGGGGCCAUCGAAGUCCUUGCGCUGCCACCCUGGGGGGAGACACGUGCCCUCCAAGACCCUGCUCACAGGCAUGCACAUGCACUGUGUCCACACACAGACUUGCAGCUCAGAAGUGGGGUUCACAGACAGCACGGGCCUGGAGACAUGCUGCAUGCUUCCCUUCCGUGUUGUUCUGUUUCAUCCCAUUUCAUUUUUCAAAAAAUGCUGCUCACAGACUGUGAAUUGAUUUGCCGGUCCCUUGGAGGGUCAUGGCUGGGUCUGAAGACCCCUGUGCUAGUGGAGCAGAGAGCACCCCAGCAUGUGGGAGUGCAGUGAGCCACUAAGCCAGGGCAUCUUCUCCUGAACACUCACUCUGUGCUGCACUCAGCCUUGCCCGCCUCAGAGACCCUCCCAGAUGCACCUUUCCGAGGCCUCAGUCUCAGCCUCUGGCGUGGAUGCUGUGCUCUUCUGCAUUUAGUCCAGCAAGAGAUUGCCUUGAAAUAUGAAUGAUGAAAUUUUAAAAGGUAAAGCAUAUAUUAGGUGCAAAUUGGAUUGUUAAAUUCUUUUUUUUUUUUUUUUGAGACAGGGUCUCACUCUGCCACCCAGGCUGGAGUGCAGUGGUGUGAUCACGGCUCACUGCAGCCUUGAUUUUCUUCCAGCAGGAAGGGACUGGGUCCCUCUGUGCAGGAGCCAUCAGAGUCCCAGCUACUUAGGGGGCUCAAGCGAUCCUCCUGCCUCAGCCCCCCAAGUAGCUGGAGCUAUAGGCACACACCACCACACCCAGCUAAUUUUUGUAUUUUUUGUAGUGGCAGUGUCUUGCCAUGUUGCCCAGGCUGGUCUCGAACUCCUGAGCUCAAGUGAUCCUCCUUUCUAGGCCUCCUAAAUUCUGGGAUUACAGGCAUGAGUCACGAUGCCCAGCUGAUUAUUAAAUUCUUAAUUCAUUUAUUUAUAUUUCUUCUCUUUGUAUUGAAAACAUUUAGUGCAUUUGAGCACCUUGCAGGCCUUUGGUCCGUUUUUUUAGGAACAUCAAGUGGUGAUUGAAUAGUUUUUAUGUUCAAGGUAGAAAAUUUUGUCAGUGGCUGAAAAUGAAAAAUGUAUAUUACAGUAUAUUACUGUAAACCAAUAGAAUUUGGAAAUUAUGUGUUUUAAUAAUUCCUUUUGUCUAGUGUUACUAACAAUAAACCUUAAUAAAGGUUAGAUUCCUCAUGUGACACUACUCAUAUAAAUAAUUUAAAACUUUCAAAACAUUCAUUUCAAAAUAUCCGUGAAUGUGGGUGGCCCAGACAGACUGCCUGCAGAGGAGCAGUUGAGUCCUUGUCAGCUGAGCUGCCGCGUUCAAGAGACCCACCGAGGAGCAGAGGUUGUGUGGACUUAAGUUACAUUUUAAAAUACUUCGUCAGUUUCUUUAAAACAGAAAUGUGUUUACUUGAGUGUAAAUUCCAAUUCUGGAGGCAUGUUAUAGAAAUUUUUAGAGCUGUUUAAUUACGGUAUAUGUUUAAAUUGUAAGCACCGAAAAGUGCUGACUUACUGGGGUCUUUUUCCAUGGGUGGCUUUGUUUUUGUGGCUGUACUUUUUUUGUAAGUAUAAUGUGUAUAUAUGGAAAUUUGGGAAGAAUCCAAGAAGUAUAGGCCAAUGAAAACAAGUUAUUAAUACAAAUAGUACUGUAUAUGAGAGUACACAUUAGGAAUGCUGUGCUUUAAUGCAUAAACAUGUUUACAGUGGUCCACAUGUGCCAGGAGAUGUGGGAAUGGCUACCCCUGAAGUCAUAUGGAGAAAUGGGGUCCUCAUCGCACACCAUACACAAACAUCAUCUCACAAAUGGAUUAAAGACACUUAAGACCUGAAACCAAAAAAACUCCUAGGAGAAAACACAGGGGAAAGCUCCAUGACAUCAGUUUCGGCGAUGAUUUUUUUUUGGACAUGACACUAAAAGAACAAGCAACAAAACUAAAAGUAAACAGGUGGGAUUACAUUGAAGUAAAAAGUUUCUGCACAACAAAGGAAACAACCAACAAAAUGAAAAACGAACCUGUGAAUGGGAGAAAAUACUUGCAAACUGUAUAUCCAGUAAGGGGUUAAUAUCCAAAUACAUAAGGAACUCAUACAACUCAGUGGCAAAAACCAAAUAACCCAAUUGAAAAAUGGCAAAGAGCCAUAGUAGACAUUUUUCCAGAGAAGCUCUACAGAUGGCCAACAGGUAUAUGCAGAGGUCUCAGCAUCACCCAUCACCAGAGAAAUGCAGUCACAACAGUGAGCUGUCACUGCAUGUCUGUAGAAUGGUUGUUAUCAGAAAGGCAAAAGAUAACAAGUGUGGGUGAGGAUAGGAGAAGAGGGAACCCUUGCACUGUUGGUGGGAAUGUAAAUUGUACAGCCAUUGUGGAAAACAGCAUGGAGGUUCCUUGAAAAAUUAAAUAUGGAACUACCAUAUGAUCCACUACUGGGUAUAUCUCCAGAGGAAAUAAAAUCAGUCUCUCAUAGUUGUGCUCCCAUGUUCAUGGAAGUGUUAAUCACAAUAGCUAAGAUAUGAAAACCUAAGGGAUAAAGGAAAUGUGCGAUGUGUGUGUGUGUGUGUGUGUGUGUGUGUGUGUGUGUGUGUUUAGAGAGAGAAUGAGAAUAGCAUAUUCUGCCUUAAAGGAACUCCUGCCAUUUGCAACAACAUGGAUGAAGCCAAACAUGUGUGGCUUCACUUACAUGUGGACUCUAAAAACAUUGAAUUCAUGGACGCAGAGAGUAGAUUGGUGCUUACCAGUGCCUGGCGGUAGUGGUGGAGAGAUGUUGGACACAGGAUACAGACUUCCAAUUAUAAGAUGAAUAAGUUCUAGAGACCUGAUGUACAGCUUGGUGGUUGUAGUUAAUAAUGCUGCAUUUAUUGUAUGCUUGAAAUUUGCUAAGAGAGUAAAUCUUAAUUUGCUAAGAGAAUAGAUUCUCACCACACACAAAAAAGGCAACUAAGUGAGGUGGUGGAGGUACAUGUUAAUUCACUUGAUUGUGAUAAUCAUAUUACAGUGUAUACAUAUAUUAAAAUAUCAUAUCACAUACAUUAAAUAAAAAUUUAAUAUUA